AGGCCCUGGAGCGGACGGUUCCUACUGCGGCUGGGCACCGGCUCCGCUCCCGCGUCUGCCCGCGCUCCAGCUGCGCCUGGCCCGGCCCCGGCCCGGCUCGGCGUGGCCCCGGCCUCCAAGCGAAGGCGCCGCUGCCGCUGGGCCGCUCCCAGGGCCAUGAGGAAGCGGCGGCAGCCACUGCGGCCCGCGUCAAGGUGACCGGCCGGGACUGCGGCGGCGGGGAGAGCGGCGGACUUCUCCAGACAGGUUAUGUUACCUGCAGAGGCUGCCCUGAAGCUCCCUGUGGCCUGGAGACUAUGUACAAGAGGAAUGGUCUGAUGGCUAGCGUGUUGGUCACCUCUGCCACUCCACAGGGCAGCAGCAGCUCGGACUCUCUGGAGGGCCAGAGCUGCGACUAUGCCAGCAAGAGCUAUGAUGCCGUUGUCUUCGAUGUCUUGAAAGUGACCCCAGAGGAGUUUGCUAGCCAGAUUACAUUAAUGGAUAUACCUGUGUUUAAAGCUAUCCAGCCGGAGGAACUAGCCAGCUGUGGAUGGAGUAAGAAGGAGAAACACAGUCUUGCCCCUAACGUUGUGGCCUUUACCCGGAGGUUUAACCAGGUCAGUUUUUGGGUUGUACGAGAAAUUCUAACAGCACAGACUUUAAAAAUAAGGGCAGAAAUCCUCAGCCAUUUUGUGAAAAUAGCCAAGAAACUUCUAGAACUCAACAACCUUCAUUCUCUCAUGUCUGUGGUAUCAGCAUUACAAAGUGCUCCCAUCUUCAGGCUGACAAAAACCUGGGCUCUUUUAAAUCGAAAAGACAAGACUACCUUUGAGAAAUUGGACUACCUGAUGUCGAAAGAAGAUAAUUACAAGCGGACACGGGAAUAUAUCCGAAGCCUGAAGAUGGUUCCAAGUAUUCCCUAUCUAGGAAUCUAUCUUCUGGAUUUAAUCUACAUUGAUUCUGCAUAUCCUGCCUCAGGCAGUAUCAUGGAAAAUGAACAAAGAUCCAAUCAGAUGAACAAUAUUCUUCGAAUAAUUGCUGAUUUACAAGUUUCCUGCAGCUAUGAUCACCUCACCACCCUGCCCCAUGUGCAGAAGUACCUGAAGUCCGUACGCUACAUUGAAGAGCUCCAGAAGUUUGUGGAAGACGACAACUACAAACUGUCGCUCAGAAUCGAACCAGGAAGCAGCUCUCCAAGACUAGUCUCUUCCAAGGAAGAUCUUGCAGGUCCCUCUGCUGGCUCCGGUUCUGCGAGGUUCAGCCGGAGGCCCACCUGUCCUGACACAUCUGUUGCUGGCAGCCUCCCCACACCUCCAGUCCCCAGACACAGGAAGAGCCACAGCCUAGGCAACAAUAUGAUGUGUCAGUUGAGUGUAGUUGAGAGUAAAAGUGCGACAUUCCCAUCGGAGAAAGCAAGGCACCUACUGGACGACAGUGUCCUAGAGUCCCGCAGCCCCCGAAGGGGCCUGGCUCUGACCUCCUCCUCUGCUGUCACCAAUGGACUCUCCCUAGGCAGUAGUGAGAGCUCAGAGUUUAGUGAAGAGAUGUCUUCAGGGCUGGAAAGGGGACGUCUCUAUGCCACCCUGGGGCCCAACUGGCGGGUUCCAGUUAGGAAUUCUCCCAGAACCCGGAGCUGUGUCUACAGCCCCACCGGCCCGUGCAUCUGUUCUCUGGGGAACUCCGCAGCUGUGCCCACCAUGGAGGGGCCUCUGAGAAGAAAAACCCUGCUCAAGGAAGGGCGGAAGCCUGCGCUGUCCUCGUGGACCAGGUACUGGGUCAUACUCUCAGGAUCCACCCUCCUGUACUACGGAGCCAAGUCCUUGCGGGGCACAGACAGAAAACACGUUUCCAUCGUGGGCUGGAUGGUGCAGCUGCCCGAUGACCCCGAGCACCCAGAUAUCUUCCAGCUGAACAACCCUGACAAAGGCAAUGUUUACAAGUUUCAGACUGGUUCCCGAUUUCAUGCAAUACUGUGGCACAAGCAUUUGGAUGAUGCAUGUAAAAGCAACAGGCCUCAGGUAAAGUCAUCAAAAUCCUGCUUGUCACCUGAAAUAUCCUCUCCCACCCUUGGAACUAAGGGUCUUUAGAAAACAGGGUUCCCUUCUUCUUUCAGAGCCCAUUAGCCACACUCUCAGAUACCCUCUUCUGAUCAGCAUCUUCCCUUGAGACAAGGCACCCCCUUGCUCAGCUUAGAACUAAGCCCAGCUCCAGACCAGAACUUUGAAUCUGGUUCCUGUGUCUUUCCCACAAUAGGAAAUGCCACAGAAACACCCACUGGGGGAUGAUUAUGAGCAGCUGUGAUAUCACCCCAGGAUCAGGUUCUAGCAUCUAUUUAGGUCAUCCCUGCCAAGAGCUGACUUCAUGGGAAUACUCCAGACUCACUAAAGGGCCUCCCUGCCCCACAACCCUUGGGAAUAAUGCGGCUAGCUAACUUACUGACAGCCAGCCAUGGACCACGCAAAGCUGCUGGUGAAAGGGGGUCCCUAGCUUCUCAGUGUGUUUGAGCCAGCAGGAUCUGUCUUGACAUAGGCCCUCUCUGGCCUGGCUCAUGGUAUGGCCCCCUCCCCUGGUCGCCCCCAGCCGUCCCACGAAGGGUGUUAUGCGAAAUGUUUCCCAUGCAGGAAUUGGCUGAAUUCUCUCAACAUCCCUGUGAGGUAGAUUCUCUUACUGUCUCCGUUUUAUGCUGAGGGUCCUGAGGCUCAGAAAGGGGCAGACACACAUUUAAGGUCCCACAUUAGUGAGCAGUGGAGCUGGGAUUGAACCCAGGUCUGCCUGACUCCCCCGAUUGUCUGCUUGUUGCCCCUGAGCCCUCCUGCCUCUCCUGCCUCCACUUCCCUGGUAACCCCUGCAGCUGAGCAAAAGACUGGAAGCACAUCCCCAGCUGUCAAGGCUUAUGAGAGAAAUGGCUACCUGAGCCCUCAGCAGCAGAUGGGGGCGGGCUGAAGCCUCCUGCUCCCUGGGGGUCAGGUGGGCAGCACUGAUGCUCCUGUCCCUAAGUGUCCAUGUGUGUUUUCCCCAGGGAUCAGCCAGAGGAGGAGCGGGGGAAGCAGGAGUCCUCUCCUAGCCCAUCUUGGGAGGGCUAGGCGCAUGGCAUAGAGGGUGGCGCUUCAAGGAGGACAGUUAGGCGUAGUGCCUGGGAGUAGACUCAGCAGGCCCCUUGCAGGCAGCAGCUCUGAAGUCUGGGGGACCUCAGCAAAGGCAAGUUCAUACCAGGCAUUUGGGUCCAGGAGGAUGGGGACUUCAUGGUGCCACGUGGCACAGUCACAGACUUCCUGGUCCCUCCAAGUGGUUCUGGAAGCUGAAGGGAGGUCUCUAGUGACAGUGACAGGUCCUAGGGCUCUGUGCUCAGCUCGGUCUGUAACACAGAUGAGGACAAAUACAAGAAGCUGAUUGCAAUUACAGAUGAUAAGUUAGAAAGCAGAAUUAGCAAGUUCUCAGAAUUAGUCCUCGACCAACUAAAACAGGACAAGACCAAUACAAGAAUAAACAUGAGGUGCCACAGGGAGGUUCCAAAUAGAUUGCACUUGAUUCCCUUGACUCACCCAUCUGACUUCGGGGAAUUUGUCAUAGGGAUGUGUACACACAUGUGCUCAAAGAUGUGUUUAAGAAUGUUCACUGCAGCAUUGUUCUUGAUAGGAACCAAAACCCUGGAAGCCUCUGUGACCCUUAGGGGGACCCUAUUGUGUGACACUUGAUAGUUAUUAGAAAGAGGCAGAUCAGGGCAAAAACAUUUGGAAAGGAUGAUCUCAUCUGUAUAAAAGUUCUAAGAUGAUACACAAGAAAUGGUAAUUCUGUAGCUUCUAGAGAGCUUUAUGUAUAGUUUGUACACUGAAUAAAUGUAAUUGGCCAUCCGUAUGACAGGAAGACAAGGGUUUUGGUCGGCAGCCAUCUCAAGGUGAUCCAUUGAGACAAGGUGCCAAGACCUGAACAAGGCUGCCGCCGCCCCAGCUUGCAUUAAGAGAGGAAGAGCAUCCUGGCCUCCUCCAUACUGGUCACACCAUGUGUGUCUGGGGUCCCUCAGUAGCUCUGAGGGCCGCUCUCUUAAGAGCAUAGCACACUGAAGCUCCCCUACCACACACAGGAAGCCGGAGCAGCUCCAGGUCCAACAGGAACUGACAGCCACGAGGUGGACCACCUGGAGGGCGGUGCGGGGAAGGAGGCAGGGCCCUGUGCCUGAAGCCUGGGCACCAUGGUGGCCCCAGUCAGGAGCAACAGUGGUAGCCCUGAGUAAAACCCAUUGUCCCUCUUUGGAGGAGCGGCCAGAGGAUGACAGCAGCCCCAGCAGGCAGCAGUGCCUGGGCAGGCUGAUCCAGCAGAGCACUAAUGGGUCAGUUUCAUGUAUUGGCAGAUGUGGUGUAGCAUGGCAAGGCUACAAGUUUUAAGGAUUUUUGUCUGAUUUUCAGACCUGGAGGAGGGGAUUUUUCUUCCUACUUUCCCCCUUUUUUAUUUCUAAUUUACUUUCAACCAAAUAUUCCCACUAUGUGCUAUAUGUAAUAAUAAAAAGUUGACAACAACUGAAAUAUUCAACAGCAGAGGAUGAUUUAAGUGAAUCACAGUACAUCCGUGUGAUGGAAUGCCAGGAGGGUGUAAGAAAGAGUGUGACAGAAAUGCAUCUAUUCACAAGGAAACAUCGCAGUGACUAGAGUGAUUUUCUGUUCUGUGGAACUGCAUGUCCUAAACUUGUUUUUAUUAACACUGAAUACACUUAAACCUUAUCUAUAACAUAUGUAUAGGUAUAAACAACAGCAAUAAAACACCUUAUUGCCACCAUGAGCCUAACAGCAGAGCCACCAGGGCCUUGGAAUGCUGUCCCUCACCAUGGCCUCUUCCUAAUUCGGUUUCUCUCCCUCCCACCUGUGCCCCAGCACCACUCUCCUGAUUUGUUUGCUGAUUAUUCCUUUAGAAUUGCAGGUCACGUACUUGAUUCCUUCAUGUGUUGUCUGGGGUGCAUUUUUAAACUUUCUUAUAAAUAGAACCAUAAAGAUGCAUUUUCUUGUGUCUUGCUUUUCUCCUGUAACAUGUUCCUAGGAUUCAUCUGUGUUACCACAUGUAGCAGUCAUUCAUUUAUUUUUACUCAUUUUGUUUUUAUUAGUUCUUCUGUUGGACAUCCCAGGACUGAUUUUCCGCUUUUUUGCUAUAGUGAACAGUACUGCUAAUGACCAUUCUUAUAACUGUCUCCUGGUACAUGGAGAUGCAUUUUUUUCCUAAUUCAUAGUUUGACCAAACUGACACCAAAAUGGAUUUUUUUAAAUGAAAUUAUUUCUAAUCAAAUCCUCCCACAGCAGUGCUGAGGGAGGAGGUCUGGGGCUGAGGACCUGUUGGCAGCUUUUGGGGGUGGCAGAAACACUCUGACCUUGGGGCUAGUGGUCCCGCCAGUAAAGGGGUCUAGGAUCUUGUCCUGAGGGCAGAGCUGUGGGAAGGUCUUGGGGUUUCUGAUAUCCCUGAACUGACUCUUUCUCCCAUGCUUCCCUUUGCCAACUCCAGCCACCCACCCUCUGCACACACCUCAGGCCUUCAGGAUUUGUCUCUCUGCCCCAAGCGCAGUUUGAUUUUCACUGAAGGAGAUAGGUUAAGAGCAUGGGCUCUGGGUUCUUAGCCCUGCUGCUUACUUGCUGUGUACUGAACCUCCCUAAGCCUCAGUUUCCUGUCUUUGUAAUGAGGACGAUCCCAGUGCCUGCCCCAGGGGUUGAAGUGAGGACUCAAGAACGCAGUGCAUGCGGUGGAUUCAGAGCAGUGCCUGGCACGCAGCUGCCACUUCACAUGGGGUGGCUAUUGUUAUUGCCAUACCCUCUCCCUACCCAACCUGCUCAUUCCCAGACUCACGGGGAAAGGCCUGUCCCUUCCCCUAGGGACCACCACCCCUUGUCCUUCUCUGAGGUCGGAACUUUAACAAGAGGCUGAGCUUUCUCUUCUAGGUACCUGCAAACCUUAUGUCAUUUGAGUAAGUCUCUGCAGGACGUGGCAUGACUUCAGAGGCUUCUGGGAACCCAGGCUGGGCCUGGUGGUGAAGAGCAGUCCUGGGCACAGGCUGUGAGCCAGGGUGCUGGGAAACUCACAGCUGGACUCAGGGGACACGGCCUGUGGCCUCACCAUCCCAGAGGGCUUCACCAGUGUGGGAUCCACCUGUCAGUCCCCAGCGACUCUCAUGACACUCAUUCUGCAGCACCGCCUCUUGGGGCAGUGGUCAGACCCCACACGCCCUCUCUGGGCCCACCACCUGCAUCUGCGACUAGAGAGCACCCGGCCCACGUUGGGUUCUCAGUGCUUUCUACUGCACAGAGUGGACAGCGCUAACUAACCUGUGAGAGGGGCCCGAGAGAAGGAACAGCUGUGGAACAGGCUUUUUACACCCCAAGUGCAUGGGGUUGCUCGCCCACAGGGCUGCCUCAGAUUUUGUACAACCCCGAAGCGUCCUCUGCGUGUGCGUGCUGUACGUGUGUGUGUGUGUGUGAGCGAGUGUGAACUCUUCAAGAAACAUGCAUUUUGGCACAAGACUCGUGACAUCACACACUUCAUUCGCUUUGAGGCCCUGCUUUAACCUUAAGUUAUAGCCCUGUCCACCGAGGAAGGUCAGGGUGAGAGCCUAGAUUCCUCCUGUGUCAAGGGUCCCUCGCAUUCUUUUACUGUAAACAAACAAUGCCUUAAAUUGUGUCUUGUUUUCUGUUCCUAUGGGUGCUAUUCAUCUGGAAGGCCUGCUUCCAGGCCUCUUUGCUGUCAGCCCUUCUGAGACAGGACCUGGCUUCAGGACUGUGGACUGGGCUGCUGGCCUGCUUGCUUCCUCCCUUCCCCAUUCCUAGCAGGGCCUGAGGCCCUCCUCUUCUCGCCCUUCCCACCAUGCCAGAAUGGGAAGUUGUGACGUUGCAGCUCCAACCGACGUGCUCAUAGUGAUCAGCUGUGCAGGAGCCAUGAGGCACCAACCUCUCCCCGCAGGGCAAAGCCUGUGCCCCCAUCAUCUCACUCCUUUGCCUGCACUGCCAGGGUGGGGCCCACCAAGAUUCCUGAUCAUGACGGGAAGCUGAGUGACCCUGAGGCCUUAAGCUUCCCCAGUCUUGGCCCCAAAUGCAGUCACCAGCAAGUUUUCCAUUUUCCAAGUCCAAGGGCACAAUUGUUGAUGACCGUGUGACAAUAGAGCGAAGCCCCGGGGAGUGAACGGUCCAACCUCUGCAUUCAGUUAGGAGCUCUUCACAUGAAUCACAUCCUUAUCUGUCACCUUGUGUCACAUUUUAAAGUGACUUUUAUUUUGCACAAAUAAUUUUUAUUCAGAAUAAUAAAUCACUCUUUAUCAUAGUAUCUUCUCUUCCCUCUUCCCCUUUAGUUUGGAUAGCCUAACUCUGAGAAGUUAACCCUUAAACAGUUUUCUGGAAGAGACUGAAUUUCUGGGUCCUUGCAGCUGUGAUGGUUUCAGAGCUCAGACUGAUCAGGCAUCAAGCUACCCUCAAGAGUUUCUGGGCUGGAUGUUUCAGAACAACAUCUACACCAGUAAAGUGUAAUAGGUCAGUUUCAAAACGACCAAAAGACCCACCACUGUAUUUUGACCAAAUAAUGACAACUUCUUUAGAAAUUUGAAUGGCUUGGUGAGGAAAGUAGUUGUCACCAGGGCCUCAUUUUGUAGUUGAGCCUUACAAUGCUUAGUAGUUCAUCUUCUUUUUGAGCAAAGACUAGAAUACUUUCCUCCUAAGAGAAACUCCCAGGUGAUAAAAGUUGAUGCCAUCAAACCUUGACACCGGGUGCUCUGCACACCCACGCGGAUGUUGCACCUCAUUCUCCCGAUGACUAUUCAAAUCAGCAUCUAGAGGCUGAAUGACAAUGCCAAACACUCCACCUCUGAUCAGAACCAUGCAGUGUUAACACUUUAACCUACAUUGAAUCUGAUUCUACCUGUUAACUUUUAAAAAGUCGUAAGUUUGGAUGAAAGUGCAAGAUGUGGAACAUCAACUACCUAUUUUCCUUGGGUUUUUCCACUCUGCAAACUGUCCUGGUUUUUCACACCAAUGAAGUAUUAUAGAUGCCAAUCCAAAACCUCAGAAUUUCAGGCACCACAAAAACAGGUAAUUUUCUAUCCCUUAUAAGUUUGUCUUUUCUUUCAGAAACAUCUCUUAGCCUAAUUUGAAAUAGCACAAUCACAAUUCAAAAUGUUUAGUCUUCUCACUAAUUGAGUCUGCUUCCACGUCCUCUCCCAGGAACAUUCUUAGCUCGGACUCUUGAAGAAUCUCUUUAGAUUUUGUUGGCAAAAGCCUUAUAGAAGCAGUAAGAGGCUUGACCACGCCGGAAGAGUCCUGGAGCUAAAGCUGGAAGACACUCAGCUCUCUAAGCAGGGGCUCGGCCAAACAUGGGAGUUAAGUGCUGCUUGUCUUCCCAGUGUUGGUUUGAACCCUGUGAGCCUGAGACAGAGAGGGCCAGGCACCAACCACAAGGCGGGAAAGUCCAUGGGUAGACCCUCCCCCUGGAGGGAAGCAUUUCUAGUUUUUGCUCCUUGACUGUCCAGAGUGUACAAAUGUUCAUAACGCCAUUGAAGGGAUUAUUUCUUGCAUGCAUAUGCUGAAUUUUUUUAAGCAAAUGGAUCAUGGCACCCCAAAAUGAAAGUUAUAGAAAGCUGUCUACAACUGUGGAGUUGGUAGCUGGUAACAUUGUUGUCUCAAGAACAACUCACCUCUCUCCCUAGGACUAAUUUUUGUCUCUCUCAGUUGAACAUGUUUUGUCAUUCAAGAUCAGUCAGGUGCAUUCUGGCAACUGACAUACUUGAUGGAGGAUUGAUUCGGUAGAGAGCAGUAGAAAUCUUGUUCUAACUGUGCCUGGUGAGAGACUUUGGCCCCCUCCCUCCCUAUAAGGCUGUGGAACCUGAGGAAGUAGAUACUUGAAGAGAUUCUGUUUAGGAAGAAACUCACUCUCUUUUGCCAGUUGAAUUUAUAGAGCAUUUUUUUUCUUACCAAGAUGGCCAGUAUCAUUUUACCCCCACCUCCCAAGCCCCAAGAGGUGUACCUUUUCAGAUGCCAUUUUACAGGCGGAAAUGCUCCAUGAAACAGGAAGCCACUUGCAAGCAACAUCUGCUCUGUUCCUCAGGUGGGGCCCAGAGCCCUUCCCCGAGACUGCUGAUGUCUGUAACCACUGGGGAGCACUGCCAAAAAUACAGCUUUCUGGUUUGUGAGCCCAUAAAUGACUUAAAUCAGCUUUACAUCAUUUUUACAUAUCAAGUGGUUUCAUGUUAAAAAACAAACUCCUAGUCCUUUAGAAAUAACAGAUUCUCUGCACAAAACCACCCAUUCAUUCAUUUAUUCAUUCACAGCACUAGCAAGUGCUGCCUAUGCUGAGAACAAGUCAGAUCUGAUCCCUGCCCUCAUGGACCUGACCACUCAACAAACAGUCCCCACCACACCUAUCUCCUUAGGCAAGACUUUGCCUCUCUCCUAGUCCUGAGUAUAAAUCCUGUGCAUAGAUUCCUCUAGAAAGGCAUCAAAAGGCUCAACAGACUGAAUGGCCUCUUGGUCUGCGAAAAUUCAGUUGCAAUGAGGAUGAAGUCACUAUCCUAGAGGCUGCUUGGCCCAGAAGAGCCAGGCACAGAGCUGCAGUUGGGCACGCCAAGGAUUCCAAAGGUGGAAUGAGAGAGUAGGGUCAAACUGUCACAGUAUCUGCUCCAUAGGUUUCUGUUUUUAAUUUCAAUGUUAAAUACAACUACAAUAUGAGCGAGAACUGCAUUUUCUUGGGUGUUGAGAACUUGUACCAUGGACUUCAGACCGCCUUGCAGCCGUAUGCUGCACAAGCGUGUACACCCCCUGGGCAGCCUCAAAACCCCGCUUACAGCAGCAACACAGGAGAUCAUCUGUCCAUUUUAGAACCAUUAAUCUCUUUAUCCAUUGCUGAACGACUGUGACUAUUCAGUAACGAAGUAAUAGUAAUUAAUUAGUAUGGUAUAAUCUUUAAUAAAUUUCGUGCCAAAAUGCAUGGUUUUCCACUUAGCAUUCAAAAUGUUGCAUAGAGAGUAGUUUUCAAUUUCUUAUGUACUCUUCGAAGUAAGUUGAAAAUCAGUUUCUACAUUUUAAUUCGUUUCCUGUUAAAUCUGUUGCACUCUCCUGGGCUGUCUUUUUCUCCAGCAGACCCCUGCAUGCAGUUGUGUAAGGACUUUCUCUAAUUCUUGUGAAUCGUCUCACCCGCAGUAACCACUGAACGUCAAUCAGCCCUCCAUGGGGUUCUUUCGAUUUUUGGUGAAGUAUUUUGUUACCUCAGUCUUGUAUCAAGUUGCUGUAUUUUUCAGCUUGUUACAUUGAUAAUAAUUAUUUCACUAAUUAAAUACUUUAAUGUACAAACAUCUUUGUUUACUUUGAAAUUAAAUGUGUUUUCCAAUGAA